ACUCACGCGCGCGCGCCGCUACUCACUAGCAACCCUUGGUGUCCGCAGCCCGUGUGGGACGGCGACUGCGACGGCUGCCCCCGUGGCUGCCGUGUGGCCUUGGCAUCCGUCCGGCUGCUGCAACCCGGGCCGCGGUGGCUUUUGCUGGAAGGCGUUGCAGCGGGGUGAUACCGGCACCCGGCGACGAGGCGUCCGCUCGUUUGCCUCGGCCGUGCCUCCUCCCCCUUCUCCUCUGCCGACAGAUGGAGCUUUGCUGGUUCCAGUCGCGCGGGCUCCGUGCGUCGUUCUCCUCCUCGCUGUCGGACACCCCAGCGCAGGGGACGAACAGCGUCCUCGCAAGCCCACGCGCAGGCCGGCCGACCCCGAACCUGCAGCAACCGUCCCUGCUGCCGCUGCUGCAGGAAAAUAAAUUGUCACUGCGAUGGUCCCGGCCUCCCCUGCCCCGGCCCCUGGGUGCCGCCUCCGCCUCUGCCUCCGCCCCCUCCUCUGUGGCGGCGGCGGCGGCUUCCCGCAUUCUGCAGAAAAAGCUCGCAGGUGGAAGGAAGCAGGGCCCCUGCGGAUGGCCUAGAGCCCGAGUGAAGCGGUUGGGUGCGACUUUCGCAUCUGAAACCCUGCACGUCUUCUCCCCAGACCGGAACCACCUAAACUCCCUUUUGCUCCACCAUCAAUUUCACCGAGAUGGACAGGAGUGGUGCCUUUUAAGACUGCACAGUACACAAGCCUUGAUGCAGCUGACCGUUAAACUGUCACUGGAGUCUGGGGAAGGAUAGGGUUUUGGUGAAAAUCCCACUUAUACUUCAUGUUAGGAUUCCCUUUUUGAUAUUUAUCCACAACUGGCUACGCCCACUAUUAAGCAUCUUAGCCCUUCCCCCUACCCCCAAUUUGUGUGUACUUGGAAAAUAAGAAGUAUUAGAAUAUCUCCUGGAUGUUA